AGUCGUCCCGCGCCGGAGCCGGCCCCGUAGCGUGCCAUGGCCUGCUACAUCUACCAGCUGCCCUCCUGGGUGCUGGACGACCUGUGCCGCAACAUGGACGCGCUCAGCGAGUGGGACUGGAUGGAGUUCGCCUCCUACGUGAUCACAGACCUGACCCAGCUGCGGAAGAUCAAGUCCAUGGAGCGGGUGCAGGGUGUGAGCAUCACGCGGGAGCUGCUGUGGUGGUGGGGCAUGCGGCAGGCCACCGUCCAGCAACUUGUGGACCUCCUGUGCCGCCUGGAGCUCUACCGGGCUGCCCAGAUCAUCCUGAACUGGAAACCGGCUCCUGAAAUCAGGUGUCCCAUUCCAGCCUUCCCUGACUCUGUGAAGCCAGAAAAGCCUUUGGCAGCUUCUGUAAGAAAGGCUGAGGAUGAACAGGAAGAGGGGCAGCCUGUGAGGAUGGCCACCUUUCCAGGCCCAGGGUCCUCUCCAGCCAGAGCCCACCAGCCGGCCUUUCUCCAGCCUCCUGAAGAAGAUGCCCCUCAUUCCUUGAGAAGCGACCUCCCCACUUCGUCUGAUUCAAAGGACUUCAGCACCUCCAUUCCUAAGCAGGAAAAACUUUUGAGCUUGGCUGGAGACAGCCUUUUCUGGAGUGAGGCAGACGUGGUCCAGGCAACCGAUGACUUCAAUCAAAACCGCAAAAUCAGCCAGGGGACCUUUGCUGACGUCUACAGAGGGCACAGGCACGGGAAGCCAUUCGUCUUCAAGAAGCUCAGAGAGACAGCCUGUUCAAGUCCAGGAUCAAUCGAAAGAUUCUUCCAGGCAGAGUUGCAGAUUUGUCUUAGAUGCUGCCACCCCAAUGUCUUACCUGUGCUGGGCUUCUGUGCUGCAAGACAGUUUCACAGCUUCAUCUACCCCUACAUGGCAAAUGGUUCCCUACAGGACAGACUGCAGGGUCAGGGUGGCUCGGACCCCCUCCCCUGGCCCCAGCGUGUCAGCAUCUGCUCAGGGCUGCUCUGUGCCGUCGAGUACCUGCAUGGUCUGGAGAUCAUCCACAGCAACGUCAAGAGCUCUAAUGUCUUGCUGGACCAAAAUCUCACCCCCAAACUUGCUCACCCAAUGGCUCAUCUGUGUCCUGUCAACAAAAGGUCAAAAUACACCAUGAUGAAGACUCACCUGCUCCGGACGUCAGCCGCGUAUCUGCCAGAGGAUUUCAUCCGGGUGGGGCAGCUGACAAAGCGAGUGGACAUCUUCAGCUGUGGAAUAGUGUUGGCCGAGGUCCUCACGGGCAUCCCUGCAAUGGAUAACAACCGAAGCCCGGUUUACCUGAAGGACUUACUCCUCAGUGAUAUUCCAAGCAGCACCGCCUCGCUCUGCUCCAGGAAGACGGGCGUGGAGAACGUGAUGGCAAAGGAGAUCUGCCAGAAGUACCUGGAGAAGGGCGCAGGGAGGCUUCCGGAGGACUGCGCCGAGGCCCUGGCCACGGCUGCCUGCCUGUGCCUGCGGAGGCGUAACACCAGCCUGCAGGAGGUGUGUGGCUCUGUGGCUGCUGUGGAAGAGCGGCUCCGAGGUCGGGAGACGUUGCUCCCUUGGAGUGGGCUUUCUGAGGGUACAGGCUCUUCUUCCAACACCCCAGAGGAAACAGACGACGUUGACAAUUCCAGCCUUGAUGCCUCCUCCUCCAUGAGUGUGGCACCCUGGGCAGGGGCUGCCACCCCACUUCUCCCCACAGAGAAUGGGGAAGGAAGGCUGCGGGUCAUCGUGGGAAGGGAGGCUGACUCCUCCUCUGAGGCCUGUGUUGGCCUGGAGCCUCCCCAGGAUGUUACAGAAACUUCGUGGCAAAUUGAGAUCAAUGAGGCCAAAAGGAAACUGAUGGAGAAUAUUCUGCUCUACAAAGAGGAAAAAGUGGACAGCAUUGAGCUCUUUGGCCCCUGAUGACCGGAACACAGCUGAGGACCCUUGUCCUCAGUUGGAAAGAUGAGCAUCAGAUCAAGAAAAAGGUCUGAGGCAGAAUCCAAGAUCUGCCAGGAAACACACAACAAAACAUCUGCUGUCCUGGGUGGGAGGGAAACUUCAUUUCACUGGAAUGAGUUGGGAGAGAAAGGCCCUCAGCUUUUAGAGACACAAAAAUCCAUGAAGUCUCUUCCUUUCUGGGCUUUGUUAGUCAGAGCAGGGGAUCAGAGGAGACUGAAGCAGAAACCCUGCACACGGGCCCAGGAUGUGGCUGAUUUUGUGGUUCCGGGGAGUAUGUGAUGAUAAUCACCCCCAGCAGAUUCCAUUACCUCAGCAGCUCUUGUUCCCCCGCCACUGGCAGUUCUGCAAUGCCAUAGCAUUUUCCAGAGCUAAGAUCUCUGGGUUGUAUUUGCUGACAGCCUGCAAGCUUGCAUGCUCUGAAAGAUUUUUUUUAGUUUUUAAUUUUUUUGUAGAGAUGGGGUCUCGCUUUGUUGGCGCAAUCCUCCCACCUCAGACUCCCAAAGUGCUGGAAUUACAGUUGGGAGCCACUGUGCCUGGCCUGGAAGACUUUCAACUUGUGUCUCAGUGCAGUUCUUGACUCACCUCUCUGGGCCUCAGGUUCUACAAAUGCCAGACACCUAGCGAAGAGCUCUGCAGGCUUUCCACUGCCUGUAUUGGAAAUCUUGCAAUUCACAUAAUUAUUCAGUCACUGCCUGGUACCUUUAUCUUCCCAUCCCACUAAUGUUAGUGUUUUUUAAUGGAGCUUUUAUUCUGAGAAUAUGUGUUUGUCUGUUUGUUUGUUUUUUGAGACAGAGUCUCACUUUGUCACCCAGGCUGGAGUGCAGUGGCACGAUCUCAGCUCACUGCAAGCUCUGCCUCUCAGGUUCAAGUGAUUCUCCUGCCUCAGCCUCCUGAGUAGAUGGGACUGUAGGCACCUGCCACUAUGCCUGGCUAAUUUUUGUGUUUUUAGUAGAGACAGGGUUUCACCAUAUUGGCCAGGCUGGUCUCGAACUACUGACCUCGUGAUCUGCCCGCCUUGGCCUAUCAAAGUGUUGGGAUUACAGGCUUGAGCCACCGCACCCGGCCGAGAAUAUGUGUUGUUAUUUAUGACUGGAUUAUGAAGAAUCAGGAGAAUGCAUUUCAUGUCUGAUUCUGCUGCUAAUUAAGUCAAUCAUUUAAUUUUUGGGACCUCAGUUUCUUUGUAAGUAAAAUAACACCUGCUUGUUCUUCAUCCCUGGGCUGUUGGGAGGAACAGAUGAGACAGUGGCUAUAGAAGCACUUGGAAAAUGCACUUGUCCUGUUUUGUAAAAUAAAAAGGUAUUAAAUGUGUAUUUCUGCCAUGUACCUAAUGAUUAUUCAGUGCGUAUAUAUCUGAAAAGUCAUGUUGCAAAUCUUUCUGUGAAACAGAUGCUAUUUUAAAUUCACUGGGAGAAAUAUCCUAUUUAAAGUAAUCUAUAGUAAUUUCUUUUUAUAUAAUAAAAAUAUAUUUGUAAAGUCGA